CCUUGAGCUAAGAAUAGUUUUUAUGUUUUUAAAGGGUUCUUUAAAACAACAACAAAAUAUAAGGACAGAGACUAUAUGUGCCCCGCAAAGCAUAAAGUAGGAUUUACCACUGCUGAUAUUAAUGUGGAAAUUUUUCUUAAAAAUUAGGUUUUCUGUAAGUAACUUCAAAACAAAGAUUUAAAACAAAGCCUGAUUAGUUGAGCAAAUUUAUUAGAUUGGUGCAAAAGCAAUUGAUGUUUUUACUAUUAAAAGUAAUGGCAAAACCGUAAUUACUUUCUGCCCCAACCUAAUAUAUCAAAAGCUUUUCAAACUUGUGUGUUUCAAAUAACUUCUUUAAAUUGCCCAAUAUAUUUUCACUCUCCUUUUAAAAUACCAGUUUUGGGUGGAGGAUAAGCUGGUUAAUGAAAUUCUUAUAAUAUGUGGGAAUGUUGCAGCUACAGAACUGCAGACAGUUCUUAGGUGAAAAAGAAGUGGUGUUUUUAUUCAAAUACAAAAUUAGGGCACUUAACAGUCACCCAAAAGGUCAAGAACCAGAGGAACUGAUGUAGGAAUAAUAUAAGUGGUCACUCCCAGGAAAUGGCAUAUGAAUGUUGUUUUUUCUUUUCUUUUUUUUUUUUUUUUUUUUUUUUUUGACCAGCUACCUUGGAGUUGAGCCUUAUCCAAAGUAGCAGUAGAGCAUGUUUCCAAACUUCAAUCUUACCACUUGAUGCAUUUUCCAAAGUGCUAUGAUUUGAGUGUGUUCCCCAAAGUUCAUGGGUUUGAAACAAUUGCCAGUGCAACAGUGUUGAGAGAUGGGGCCUUUAAGAGGUAAUCAAGAGGGACUUUAAGAAGCUGUGGCUUCAUAGCUGGGUUAAUAUUAUUAUCAUGGGAGUGGGUUUGUUAACAAAAACCAGUUUGGCCCUCUCUUGCUCUCUCUGUCUCCAAGUGAUACCUUCAACUAUGUUAUGAUGCAGCAAGAAGGCCCUCACAAGAUGCAGCCCCUUGAUCUUGGACUUCCCAGCCUCCAGAACUGUGAACCCAAUACAUUUCAGUUCUUUACAAAUUAUCUGGUCGUGCGUGUUUUGUUAUAGCAACAUAAAAUGGACUGAGACAGAAAAUUGGUACUAAGAAGUGGGGCUCUUGCUGUAACAAAUAUUUGAAAAUGUGGAAGUGGUUCUGGAACUGGGUAAUGGAUAGAUGCUAGAAGAAUUUGGAGGAGCAGGUUAGAAAAAGCCUAGGUUGUUAUAAACAGAGCAUUAAGGGCAAUUCUGGUGAAGGCUCAGAAGAAGAGAGCUAGUGGUAAACUAAGAAACUUCUUAGAGAUUAAUUAAGGGCUGUGAUCGGAAUGUUGGUAGAAAUAUGGACAGUAAAGGCCAUUCUGAUGAGAUCUCAGAUAGAAAAGAGGAAUUAUUGGAAACUGGAGUAAAGGCCAUCCUUGUUAUGAUGUGGCAAAGAACUUGGCCGAAUUGUGUCCAUACCCUCGGGCUUUUAGGAAGGCAGAAUUUAAGAGCCAUCAACUAGGGUAUCUCUUGAGAGAAAUUUCUAAGCAAAAUGUUGAAGGAGCUACAUGGCUUCUAUUAACUUCAUAUAGUAAAAUGAGAGGAGAGAAAUGAUUUAAAGAUGGAAUUUAUAAUUAAAAGGGAAACAGAAAUGAGGAAUUUGAAGGAUUCUCAGCCUGGCCAUGUAGCAGAGAAUGAAAGAACAUUUUCAGGAGAGGAAACCAUAGAUGUGGCCAAGGAACUGAUUGAUUGAUAAGGGGAUUAACAUGGAUAGAAGGAAACCAAAGGACGAUGAGAGAAUGACCCCAAAGGUACUUUGGAAAUCACCAGUGCUCCCCUUCCAUCACAGGCCCAGAGUGCCAAGGCCUGGGGAAAGGAAAUGUCCAAAGAGAGUCCUCGGGUGCCCUUGAGACACUGGGCUUGCUGCCUAGGGCUGCUGUAAGUCUUUGCUCCCCACAUUCCCGUACGGCUCAUGCCCCCAGUUCACCCCAGGUGUCACAGCUUUGGAAGGUGUAAGCAGCAAAUCUUGGCUAUGUUCAUGUGGUAGAAGUGUGCAGGUGCUCAAAAUUCAAGAGCUGUGGGCAUAUGGCUUCCUUCAUCUAGAUUUCACGACCGCCUGGGGGCCCAGGCAGAGACUUUCUGAGGGGCAGAGCUGAUGCAGGGAGCCCCCAACUAGGGCAAUGCCUAGUGGAGCUGUAGAAGUAGGGGAGCAUGCAGCUUCAGGCUGGGAAAGCUGCAGGCACAAGACCAACCCUUGGAUGAACUGAACCCAGCAAAGCCAUUGGGGUGGGGUUACCUGAGGCCUUGGCGGCCCAACCCCCACCCCAGUGUACAGGGGAUUGGGGACAUGGAGUCAAAGGAGAUUAUUCUGGCAUCUUAAGAUGUAAUAUUGUUUUCCCUGUUGGGUUUUGGACUUACUCAGGACCAGUUAUCCCAUUCUCUUGCCUAUGUCUCCCUUUGGAAUGAGAAUGCCUAUUCUAUGCCUGUCCCACUAUUGUAUUUUGGAAGUGGAUAACUUGUUUAAUUUUACAGGCUUACAGCUGGAGGGAAAUUUGUCUCAGGAUGAAUUGUACCUUGAGUCUCACCCAUAUCUAAUUUAGAUUAGACUCUGGACGUUUGGAUUUUUGAGUUGAUGAUGAAAGAAGUUAAGACUUUUGGGGCUAUUGUGAUGGAAUGAAUAUAUUUCGCAUGUGAGAAGGACAUGAAUUUUUGGAGCCAAGGGUGGAAUGCUGUGGUUUGAGUGUGUCCCCCAGAAUUCAUAUGUUGGAAACUCAAUCCUCAAUGCAACAGUAUUGAGAGGUGGAACCUUUAAGAGGUGAUUAGGUCAGGAGAGCUCUGCCCUAUGAAUAGAUUAGUAUCCUUAUCUCGGGAGUGUGUUGGUUAUUGGGAGAGCGAUUUUUUUUUUUGAGACGGAGUUCCGCUCUUGUUGCCUGGGUUGGAGUGCAAUGGCGCCAUCUCAGCUCAUGGCAACCUCUGCCUCCCAGGUUCAAGCGAUUCUCCUGCCUCAGCCUCCCGAGUAGCUGGAAUUACAGGCAUGUGCCAUCAUGCCCAACUAAUUUUGCAUUUUUAGUAGAGACGGGAUUUCUCCAUGUUGGUCAGGCUGGUCUUGAACGCCCAACCUCAGGUGAUCCACCCGCCUCAGCCUCCCAAAGGGCUGAGAUUACAGGCGUGAGCUACCACACCCGGCCAAGAGAAUGAGUUUUUAUAAAAGUGAAUUUGGCCAUCUCUUGCUCUUGCUCUCUCUCAGCACAGGAUGCCUUCUGUUGUCAUGAUGCAGCAAGAAGACACGCACUACGUGUGGCCCCAAGGGCUGCAGAACCAUGAGGUAGUAGAUUUCUGUUCCUUAUAAAUUACCCAGUCUUAAGUAUUCUGUUUUAGCAACACGAAAUCAGCUAAGACAAGAAGCAUCCGAGUUUUAUUGGGGAUGGAAUGAAUGGCUCCUCUGGAGCAUCCCUGCUGGUGACAAAGCCCUAGAAAACAGUGCUGGAUUUCUUUUAGGUGAAAAAUCUAGAAAAGCCCUCUUAGUGAAAACCCCAAGGGCAUGCCUGAGGAAUGCCUGAGAAGAAAGGAAGGUACACCUUCAGGAUUCUUCAAAGAGAAUUAAAUGGAUAAAACCACUGGACUUGAGUUGUUAAGGGAAUGUUAAUUUAGCUGUGGGGUAUCCUGGCCCUUGGAAUUACCUUAGCUUGUUGGUUGAUUGCAGUUUUUGUUAAUUGUUGUUGUUUUUUUGCUCUCUAUUGUUGACUUCUGUGUGUACCAGAAGGUGGGCAGGGAAAAUAAAAGGAGACAAGGAAUAAGAAUACAUUUGACCACUUGAUAGCAGCCCUGGCACAAAGCCUAGUAGGAGUAAAGGUUAAAACUGUUGGCCUAAAUCAGUGUUUAAAGUUAACUUUGAGUUAGGGCUGUCCUUGAAAUGGAUUGUCCUUUGCUCUCAUGGAUUCUUGUGCAUAACUGAUAAAAAAUAUUCUCAUACAAUAAAUUGCACCAAUAUCAUUUUGUGAAUGUGUUGGUGGGUUGCAGGGGGCGCGUUAGGGGAAGCUGCCUCCUUGCAGCUUUUGUUUUAUACGUAUUUAAGCACUAAAUAAAAAUCUAUUUUGUCUCUUUUCCCUUGCUAAGUCUCUUGUCUCCCACGGCCCUUUUCUUUCUGGAUAUAUGUAUAUUUUUAGUAAGUAAAGGACUUACUGUAUGAAGUUUUUCUUUGGCAGACAGAAUGAUGAUGACUAUAAUAUGUUUAUUACAAGGUACAUCAUGCCAAUGCUCUUGGUGUGUGUGUGUGUGUGUGUGUGUGUGUCUACAAAGAAAUGUAUCAUUUUAUGUAUAAGCUAAGAUUUUGAUAAGUAGUCAUUUAUCUAUCCAUAGAAUGCUAUUUCUUAGACUGUAGAAUGCAUUGUUAUAUGGUUAGGGCUAUUGGGGGUGUUCAUUUUUGUUUAGGUUCUUUGACCUAGUAAAGACUUCCUGGUGAUUUCAGUAGUUUGGUAAUUUAUUACUGAUCUUCUAAGAAGUAUUGGUAAUGUUAAAAUGAAAACAUUUAUACAAAAAGAAAUAAAAGUCAAGGAAGCAGAUAAUCAACCGAUUUAUCAGCCUUAGCAGACAAUUUUUCUGAUAACGAUGUGGUAGCCAUGGUAAAUUUACUUCUGAUUGCUUGAGGGGACAGAUUCUAUGUGCCUUUUGUAAUAAGAGGUGCAUGAAAGGGUAAGGGAGCAAGUAAUCAAUCCGUGGACUAACCAGUCCCAUUUUGGUCUUUAGAUUGGCCUUUUGGUGAGUAAAUUCAAGCUAUCUUUUCAACAAAAGAAAAAUUUUGUUAUUAAUUUGCUGAAACGUGAGUAAGGAUGUAAGGAUGAGUAUAUCUUUUUGUUUGGAUAUCUCUAAGUAGCCCUAGUAAGGGAAGGCCUCUUUUGGUAAUGUCUUUUUUUUUUUUUUUUUUUUUUGAGACAGGGUCUCACUCUGUUGCCCAGGCUGGAAUGCAGUGGUGCAGUCGUGACUCACUGCAACCUCUGCUUCCUGGACUCAAGUUAUCCUUCUGCUUCAGCCUCCCGAGUAGCUGGGACCACAGGCAUGCACCACCACACUUGGCUAAUUUUUAUAUUUUUGGUAGAGAUGCGGUUUCACCAUAUUACCCAGGCUGGUCUUGAACUCCUGAGCUCAAGUGAUCCGCCAGCCUUGACCUUCAAAAGUGCUGGGAUUAUAGGUGUGAGCCACCAUGCUUGGCCUAUUUUUUUAAACCUUUCAUUUGAAAGAAAUUUGAGUAAAAUUGAGAGAUAAGCAAAAAUUUAUUAGUCCACUCAUAGUCCUUCCAGCCUCACAGGACUUAACACUGAUCAGCAAUGUGGUCGGUUUUAUGUAAUAAUAUCCAGCUUAUUACAAAAACUACAUUACAAACUGAGGCUAUAGUUGAGAAUCCAGAGGUGAACAAAUUCAGGAAAAAUGCCUCAGGCCUUCAUCCAAAUAUACUUAUAUUAGUUUUCUUGGGUUGCUGUAAUAAAGUAUCACAAACCAGUGCUUAAACAACAGAAAUUUAUUGUCUCACAAUUCUGGAGGCUAAAAGUCUGAGCUCAAGGUGUCCACAAGGCCACUCUCGCUCUGAAGGCGGUAGGGAAGGGUCUGUUCCAGACCUCUCGCCCAGCUUCUGGUAGUUUCUAGGCUUAUGAUAGCAUAACUCAUCUCAUGGUGUUCUUCCUGUGUGCAUGUGUGUCUCUGCAUCCAAAUUUCCCCCUUUUAUAAGGACACCAGUCAUACUGGAUUUGAGUCCACCCCAAUGACCUCAUCUUCACUUGAUUAUCUGCAGAAGCCUAUUUCCCAAUAAGGUCACAGUCACAUGUACUGGGGGUUAGAACUUCAAUAUCUUUUGAGAGAACACAAUUCAACUCAUGAUACUAGGUAUUCAUUCCAAGUUUGUACACAGUUUUAAUAAGCCUGGUGAUUUUUAUCUCAGUUUAUGCAUACAAAGAGUUAUAAGUAUAGGAGAAAGAGUCUCUGCUGAGGAUAUAAUGGAGAACAAAAGUAUUCAAAAAGACUAUUAAAGUAGGAAUAAGAACUUAAAAUACAUAGUUGCUUUGGGCCACUCAAUGGAGGGACAAACUGCUGAAAAGUUCCAGUAGCUCCUGAAACACAUUUAUAUAUAACAAACAUAAUAACAGCAUCAACAUAUUAUGUUUGAGUGUGUGUGCACUUUUAAAUCCCAUCAAAUUAAAUUUUGAAAAUAUUGCGUACUUGAUGGCACUUUGAUAAUUUUUGGUUACCUGAAAAAUUAUUCUUUUGUCAAGCUCCUCACAUAUUGUCAGAUGUUCUGAAUAUUUGGGUUUCAACUUGGCUUUGUCACUCAGUAAGCAUGCAUGUUGUGUAAGCCAUUAACUUUUUGGAACUUGGGUUUUUUGGUCUGUAAAAUGAAAAGUUUGGUUUCCUAUAUAAAAUUAUUGUGAGGAUGAAAUUUGCUGAUGAAUAUGAAAACAUCUAUCAUAGCUCCAGAUGUGUUUUCAUGAUUGUUCAUUCAUUCAACAAAUGUUUAUUGGGAGCCUACUGUAUGCAGUGGCUUGUUCUAGAAUUCAUUCAUUCACUUAAUGCUGAUUGAAAAGUACCAUGAUUUAGUAGUAUUGGGACAUCUGAGCUCAAGCACUGCCUAUGUUUGGAAAUCAUCUAGGGGACCUUGGGCAAAUCUAUGGCCCUCUCUAGGCCUCUAACUAGAGACUAGUCAUAUAGAGUAGAUUUCCAAGGCUUUUCCAUCUGUAAAAUAAUUCAUAUAACAAACUUCAAGUAUAAUGAAUAGUUUUUGAUAUCGUACAGAUUAAUUGUAUUAUACUGGCAAGUUACUUUAUCCUCUGCGCCUUUGCUUUUGUCUUUGAAAGUGGGGUUAAUAGGUCUAGUACUGUUUUCUGGUUAGUAAUAGCAGUAAUAAUGAUAGUCACCCAUUAUUGAGCUCUUGGCAUUGUGCUAGAUAUUUUUAUACAUUCUUGCUUCUACAAACACGGUACAUGUUUCUCCAAAGCAUGUCGGUACCUGGAGAAACAGGUUGCAUCUUUCUAGAGAAUAAAGUUUCCUUGAUGGCACAGCUGUUUAUAGAGUGGAAUGCAGAAGUCACUUGAAAUGUUAAGCUAAAACUCAAAGAAAGUUGGGGCUUCUUAGAGGGGGCGGCGACUUUAAUACCAAGUUCCCCUGCAGUGUUGUUCUUUCUUGGCCUUUGGGGAAACUGGUGGAAAAGUUUGCAAAACAGGCUUUUUCCCUGUUCCAUGUUUGACUCACAUGAGAAAAAUAGCAUUCUAAUUUACAAUUUUGAAAAUAGUUCUUAUUUCCAUCACUGACAGAUGUUACCUUUAUGAUUGUUCAGCCUAUUCUUCCAUUUCAUUUAUGCAUUGGACAAAUAAUAAUUGACUGCCUGCUCUGUGUUCAGUACCAACCUAAAUGCCGAGGAUGCAGCAGCAACCAAAAUAAAGUCCUCCCUCGGAGCUUGUAUUCUAAAAAACAGUGAGGUUUGAGGGCAGACCUGAGGAAUUAGGGGAAUUAAGCAUGUGGCUGUUUCAGGCAGAGGAAGAGCAAUUGCAAAGGCCCUGAGGCAGGAGCUUAUUUUCCUAGUAAGGGAGAGUGUUAGGAGAGGAGGUCACAAGGAGAUGAUUAGGGAUGCCUUGAGGUUCAGGUAAGAGUUUUGUAUUUUAUACUGAGAAACAUGGGAAACCAUUGUGGAAGUUUGAGAACUUACUUUGGCUGCUGGUUGAGAAUAAUGGAGCAAGGUUGGGAAGUGAGGAGACCAGUUGGAAGGCUACUGCCAUAGUACAGGUGGGGGAUGACAGCACUGGGUACCAGGUUAGUAGUAGUGGUGGAAAUGGUGCAAAGUGGCCAGAUUUGGUACCUCUGUUGAAGGUAGAACCAACGGAAUCCGAGAAUGAAUUGGAUGUGGGGUCUGAGAGAAAGAGAAGAGUCAAGGGAGGUGGCAUGGUUUUGGGUCUAAGUAAUUGAAAGGAUGGAGGAGUUGCCAUUCCUGCUGAGACGGGCAGGUAGAGGGAGGAACACGGGCAGUUCCUCGGCCAUGGAAGGUCUGGCUAAGCACUUUAUAUGAAGAAUACUGAAACUGACUUAGCUACUUUUUCGAACUCACUCUGCAGAGGAGUGAUGCGUUCAUUUGUGUUACCUUUAUUUUACUCACGGUCAUUUAGAAUAAUGAUUUGAAAAUGUUGCUGUGUGCCAAAUGCUCGUCUUGACCCAGGAGCCCCUCCCUCCCCCCGUGUGUGGACUACUCUCGUCUCCAGACUUCCUCUCACUUCCUCAUGCCUUUGCAGCACCUUUUCCCUAGCUGGACUGGUGACAGGAAUCUGGUUGUCUUCUGCACCCUGGCAGUUUUAAAUAACUAGCAGUUCUUACAUUUUCUUCCUGGGCACGCUGACAGCGGUUGGGUGUCCUGGACAUCCGUGUUUCGAUAACUGUAAUCUCCGAGUCUCUGUCCUGUGAAGCCCAUUGCCGGCCGUGCAUUUACCUCAGACUGUGGACUUGGAGCCUUGAAGACGCGAGAGGUCUCUUAGUUUCAGGCAGACCUGGUGUGGGGGAUGUGCUAAGGCUCUCAGGCUACAAAGGGACAAUUUAAAACUUGGCAAGUAAAACCGGCCUAAAUGCGGAUGUGUUUUAUGCUUAGCAUCAUAAAAUUGAUUCAGAACAGCCUGAUAUGCGGCAGAAGAAACCUUUAUUAAACAUUAUAGAGGUCAUUGCUUUUGUCUUCCUGAUACCUCUUCCCUCUCCUUUCUUCUGUGACCCACAUUGAGCCCAUUGUAGAACCCGCCCCCUGGCUUCAGUGAUAGGCCCAUGGAGGGGAACAUGACCUCCAACAGGCCAAUCAGAGGCGUAAAGACCUUUCUCUAGUGGGAAGUCAUUGAGAGUGAAAACCCAGAACCGGUUGCAGCCAGGUUUUCAGCCUCCUGGGAAAAGUGGCCUGAGAGGAAGAGACUAGAGGCGAAUGAGAGAGAGCCCUGAUGGUGCUUUCGACAUCCUAUCUGAUGCUGGCUCCAUUGUGCCCCUUUUAUUGUUUGGUACAGGAACUGAGAAAAUUCCCUUAUUGCUUCAUGCGGUCCUGCUGGUUUUCUGUCAUUUACAACCACAGGAGCCCAGAUACCCCUACUAUGAGCAGGGAAUCAAGAAGGAACACAAAAAUGACUAACUCAUAGCCUUGCCUCCAGGUAUUUAUAAUGUAAUAGUUUGAUUUCAAAACUAGUGAGUAUGGUAAAAUAGUUGGUAAGGUCUACCUUUGACAAAUCAAUAGUAUAUUUUUAAAAUGUGAAGAUAGUGUAUUUUAUAAAAAUAUACAAUUUUUUCAUUGGGUUAAUUUAUCCAACAUAUAUCACUUGAAUAUUAGCUUUCUCCAUGACUGGCAUAUUUCCUUUUUGAUAAUUUGCUGAGGAGCAAGGCUGCUUGUUAAUGAAUUUUUGUCUACUAUUAAAAUCGCCCUCAUCCUUUGAGGUCCAUUUCCAAAGCCACCUGCACCUCUGGAGUUCAUUAUUCCCUCUUUUGUGCUUACACAACCCUUGCUGUUUCUGUAUGGUGGCACCAGUCAUUAUGCUUUGAAUGCUUGUGAAACCCUCACUCUUCUGUUGAUUAGAAACUUUUAUGCCAGAGACUGUUGUGUCUCUGUUUCCCUUUGCAGGGAACAGUUCCCUGAACAUAGUAGGUGAUCAGUAAAUGCUUGUUGAAUUAAGUCAAUUAGUAGCACUGGUUUUGCUAAUAACUUUUGUAGUAAACUUACAAACUACUUUUAUGUAAAACUGCAUGUAAAAGUUGGUUGUAUGAUUUGCAGCACUUAUUAUGAGUAUAACUGAUAAUGCUAAUGGAAAUGUAUGAUCUUAAAAGGCAUUAGAUAUUUAGCUAUAGAAGUGUAUUAGUAGGAAAGGGAAAACUUACAAGAUUUUUACAUGAAAAUAAACCAGAAGGUUGGUUGGUAGGUACCAGGUGAACAUACCUGUGGUCACAAGAAGAGAGUGUUGGAGACACUGAUUGUUAGAGAGUUGACCGUGAGAAAGCAUCUCUCCAAUCCUAUGCCAGAUGUUAGUAGGCAGGAAGAGGCGGAGGGAGAGCUCAGUGAAGGAGAACACUGGUAUGGAAACUCUUCAGAGACUCCGUCAGAAGCAUCCUAUGGGGAAGUCCAGGAGAACUAUAAGUUGUCUCUGGAGGACCGGAUCCAGGAGCAGUCCACGUCCCCGGACACCUCCUUGGGAAGCACGACUCCCAGCAGCCACACGUUGGAGCUGGUGGCACUGGACAGUGAGGUCCUGCGAGACUCACUGCAGUGUCAAGAUCACCUUUCCCCGGGAGUGUCUUCUUUGUGUGACGAUGACCCAGGCUCCAACAAGCCCCUGAGCAGCAAUUUGAGGCGGCUGCUGGAGGCUGGUUCCCUCAAACUCGAUGCUGCAGCCACGGCUAAUGGCAGAGUGGAGUCCCCCGUAAACGUUGGCUCGAACCUCUCCUUUUCCCCGCCUUCCCACCACGCCCAGCAGCUCAGUGUUCUGGCCAGGAAGUUGGCCGAGAAGCAGGAACAGAAUGACCAAUACACUCCAAGUAACCGUUUUAUAUGGAAUCAAGGUAAGUGGUUGCCAAACUCAACCACCACCUGCAGCUUGUCUCCGGAUUCAGCCAUCCUAAAACUGAAAGCUGCAGCCAAUGCCGUUCUGCAGGACAAAUCUCUCACCAGGACUGAGGAGACCAUGCGAUUUGAGUCCUUUUCCUCCCCUUUUAGCUCCCAGUCUGCCAGUUCUACCUUGGCCGCUUUGUCCAAGAAGGUCAGUGAAAGAAGUUUGACUCCUGGUCAGGAGCACCCUCCACCGGCCAGCUCCUUCCUUUCCCUGGCUUCUAUGACCUCCUCAGCGGCCCUUCUGAAGGAGGUGGCCGCAAGGGCUGCGGGCAGUCUUCUGGCUGAGAAAUCAUCGCUGCUGCCUGAGGACCCUCUACCGCCCCCGCCUUCAGAGAAGAAACCAGAAAAAGUCACUCCGCCACCUCCACCGCCACCUCCACCACCUCCACCACCACCACCACAAUCCCUGGAAUUAUUAUUACUCCCAGUUCCUAAGGGAAGAGUUUCUAAACCCUCCAAUUCAGCCUCAGAAGAGGAAAGUGGAAAGCCUUUCCAGUGUCCAAUAUGUGGUUUGGUUAUUAAAAGGAAGAGUUACUGGAAGCGGCACAUGGUGAUUCACACAGGUUUAAAAAGUCAUCAGUGUCCGCUCUGUCCAUUCCGGUGUGCUCGCAAGGACAAUCUCAAAUCCCACAUGAAGGUUCAUCAGCACCAGGAUCGGGGAGAGACCUUUCAGUGCCAGCUGUGCCCUUUUACUUCCUCACGCCACUUCAGCCUGAAACUCCACAUGCGUUGCCAUCAGCACUUCCUGAGGACAGAAGCCAAGGUGAAGGAGGAGAUCCCAGACCCAGAUGUCAAGGGAUCUCCCCACCUCAGUGACAGUGCCUGCCUGGGGCAGCAAAGGGAAGGAGGAGGGACAGAGCUAGUGGGGACCAUGAUGACGUCUAACACUCCAGAGAGGACUAGCCAGGGAGGGGCUGGCGUCUCGCCUUUGCUGGUGAAGGAGGAACCCAAGGAAGAUAACGGCCUGCCCACCUCCUUUACUUUGAAUGCUGCCGACAGGCCCGCCAACCACACAAAGCUGAAAGACCCCUCCGAGUAUGUGGCCAACAGUGCGUCAGCAUUGUUCAGCCAGGACAUCUCUGUUAAGAUGGCGUCUGAUUUUCUCAUGAAGCUGUCAGCUGCAAAUCAGAAGGAGCCCAUGAAUCUUAAUUUUAAAGUGAAAGAGGAGCCUAAGGAAGGGGAGUCCCUAAGCACGACUUUGCCUCGGUCCAGCUAUGUGUUCAGCCCGGAAUCUGAAGUGUCAGCCCCAGGCGUCUCUGAGGACGCACUAAAGCCCCAGGAAGGGAAGGGAAGUGUGCUAAGGCGGGAUGUGUCAGUCAAAGCAGCCUCUGAACUUCUCAUGAAACUCUCAGCGGAAAGCUACAAGGAAACACAGAUGGUGAAGAUUAAAGAGGAACCCAUGGAGGUUGACAUCCAGGACUCCCAUGUCUCGAUAUCACCCAGCCGGAAUGUUGGCUACAGCACUUUAAUCGGGCGAGAGAAAACCGAACCCUUACAGAAGAUGCCAGAGGGCAGAGUACCCCCAGAGAGAAACCUCUUCAGUCAGGAUAUCUCUGUGAAAAUGGCUUCCGAGCUCCUCUUUCAACUGUCAGAAAAAGUGAGCAAAGAGCACAAUCAUACAAAAGAAAACACCAUCCGGACCACGACCAGCCCUUUCUUUUCAGAAGACACAUUUAGACAAUCACCAUUCACCUCCAAUUCAAAAGAACUGCUGCCCAGUGACUCCGUGCUGCACGGAAGAAUAUCAGCUCCAGAAACAGAAAAGAUAGUCCUAGAGGCAGGAAAUGGAUUACCAUCCUGGAAAUUCAAUGACCAGCUUUUUCCCUGUGACGUGUGUGGGAAAGUGUUUGGCCGACAGCAGACAUUGUCCCGACACCUCUCGCUGCACACAGAGGAAAGAAAAUACAAAUGCCACUUGUGCCCCUAUGCUGCUAAGUGCCGUGCAAAUCUGAACCAGCACUUGACCGUCCAUUCCGUGAAGCUGGUGAGUACAGACACCGAGGACAUUGUCAGCGCCGUCACCUCUGAAGGCAGUGAUGGGAAGAAACAUCCUUAUUAUUACAGUUGUCACGUGUGUGGAUUUGAGACCGAGCUCAAUGUCCAGUUUGUCAGCCACAUGUCACUCCACGUGGACAAGGAGCAGUGGAUGUUUUCGAUCUGCUGCACUGCCUGCGACUUCGUCACCAUGGAGGAAGCAGAGAUAAAGACUCACAUUGGCACCAAGCACACAGGGGAAGACAGGAAGACCCCCAGCGAAUCAAAUAGCCCCUCUUCAUCCUCCCUCUCAGCUCUGAGUGAUUCAGCCAACAGCAAAGAUGAUUCAGAUGGCUCCCAGAAAAACAAGGGCGGGAACAAUCUGCUGGUCAUCUCUGUCAUGCCUGGGAGCCAGCCCUCACUGAACAGUGAGGAAAAGCCAGAGAAAGGGUUCGAAUGUGUUUUUUGCAACUUUGUCUGCAAGACGAAGAACAUGUUUGAGCGUCAUCUGCAGAUACACCUCAUCACCCGGAUGUUUGAGUGUGAUGUGUGCCACAAGUUCAUGAAGACCCCCGAACAGCUGCUGGAGCAUAAGAAAUGCCACACUGUCCCCACCGGUGGGCUCAAGUGCCCAUUCUGCAUUUAUUCCACCAACCGCCCCGCUGCCAUGGAGUGCCACCUCAAGACCCACUACAAGAUGGAGUACAAGUGCCGGAUCUGCCAGACGGUGAAGGCCAACCAGCUGGAGCUGGAGACGCACACCCGGGAGCACCGCCUGGGCAACCACUACAAGUGCGACCAGUGCGGCUACCUGUCCAAGACCGCCAACAAGCUCAUCGAGCACGUGCGCGUCCACACCGGGGAGCGGCCCUUCCACUGUGACCAGUGCAGCUACAGCUGCAAGCGCAAGGACAAUCUCAACCUGCACAAGAAGCUGAAGCACGCCCCACGCCAGACCUUCAGCUGCGAAGAGUGCCUGUUCAAGACCACACACCCUUUCGUCUUCAGCCGCCACGUCAAGAAGCACCAGAGUGGGGACUGCCCCGAGGAGGACAAGAAGGGCCUGUGUCCAGCCCCCAAGGAACCGGCCGGCCCGGGGGCCCCGCUCCUGGUGGUCGGGAGCUCCCGGAAUCUCCUGUCUCCCCUGUCAGUUAUGUCUGCCUCCCAGGCUCUGCAGACCGUGGCCCUGUCGGCAGCCCACGGCAGCAGCUCAGAGCCCAACCUGGCACUCAAGGCUUUGGCCUUCAACGGCUCCCCUUUGCGCUUUGACAAGUACCGGAACUCAGAUUUUGCCCAUCUCAUUCCCUUGACAAUGUUAUACCCCAAGAACCACUUGGAUCUCACAUUCCACCCUCCCCGACCUCAGACUGCGCCUCCCAGCAUCCCCUCACCCAAACACUCCUUCCUGGCCUAUCUCGGACUGAGAGAAAGAGCAGAGACUGUCUGAGGGCAGCCAUGUUCUGUACCAAAAACAGAGAGACAAAAGACAAAAAAAAAAAAAAAAACCACAAAACUUAAACACAACCCCAGCAGGUGUAUGUUGCUGCAAAACCUACAGACCCCGAUGGGUCUGGAACAUGUGUACUGUAUAUCUUUAGUAAGGAAUAGAAAAUUGGCUCUGUGUGUAUACCUAUUGCAUUGACCUGAAAGCUGCUUUAUCCAAUCUUCAGAGAGGUGACCUACUGCAUACUUCUACCUUCAGAGGCAUGCCUCCCCAGCCACCCACUCCCACUCUCAGCCCUUCUCCGUACUUUUCUCUGAAAGGAAUCUUGUCUUGUUAAACCCUAAAGAGAGUGUCCUUAAUAGCAAUCAGCACUUGUAAGCUUAUAUACUGGUGCAUUUGGUUUUCUGUUGGGUGAAUGCGGUGUGUGGGCGUUUGUGGAUUCUGAAAGAGAAAGCCGUGUGUCGUGUGCCAUGACAUUUCUAUUGCACAUUCUUUGUACUGGCUUCUUUAACAGCGAUGAACGUUCUUUUCCCUCCUGGGUUGUUCAUCCACGACAGUCUCUCCCUGUGCUCCUUCAUCACCUUUCCCUCUCUCUUUGAUGGCUACAGAGUGGUAGGGCCUGGUGCUUAGUCGAUGAAGGAAUGGUAGCCAUCUACAGUGCUGCUGGAGAUUUCCGCCAGAGCGCUGGAGACCUUGCGCUCAGAUCUUCUCUGGUGAUGAAGAGGCGAGGAAUCAAGUGACUGAUCUGGAAGAAAUAUCUCGCAGCACUGCAGCUAACAUCACAGAACUUAAGUGUGUUUUGUGUGUGUGCCCACACGUAGACAAAUGUGUACGGUGCACACACACAGUGCAUCAUUUUUUAAGGGCAGAUUAUAUAUAUAUAUGAGAUGUAUUAAUUCAGUGGUUACCAUUUGUUUGCAGGAAAAAGAAAUGUAUGGGUGAAAAAAUUUAUGGUUGAUAAAUCCAGCCAAGGAGAUUAAAAGGGGUUUGGAUAAAUUCUGGGUAUAAAUGCUCAGACUAAAAAAAAGAAAUGGCAGUUUUGCACAGUGCUAUGGUCUUGCACUAGUUUUUGUUUCUCAUCUGAAAAAAAAAAAGUAAAAUAAAAGGAAGAAAAUGUACCUUUUUUAUGGAAUGAGUAGACUGUAUGUUUGAAGAUUUAGCCACAACCUCUUUGACAUAUAAUGACGCAACAAAAAGGUGCUGUUUAGUCCUAUGGUUCAGUUUAUGCCCCUGACAAGUUUCCAUUGUGUUUUGCCGAUCUUCUGGCUAAUCGUGGUAUCCUCCAUGUUAUUAGUAAUUCUGUAUUCCAUUUUGUUAACGCCUGGUAGAUGUAACCUGCUAGGAGGCUAACUUUAUACUUAUUUAAAAGCUCUUAUUUUGUGGUCAUUAAAAUGGCAAUUUAUGUGCAGCACUUUAUUGCAGCAGGAAGCAGGUGUGGGUUGGUUGUAAAGCUCUUUGCUAAUCUUAAAAAGUAAUGGGUGAUUUAAAAAGAAAAAAGGAAAAAAAUCUUUGGCUGAAUAUGUUCAUUGCUUGUAUUUUUAAAACAACAGAAUUUCCAGUAUGAAACAGGCUGAAAGAGCAGGAAGAAAUGUUCUUUGUAUAAUAAUGGGAAGUUUGGAAUAUAAAAGUUUAUAUAUUAUUUAUCUAUUGGAGAACUGGUGUACAGGAGGAACAUUUUCUUACUGUGUUGCUGUUUUCCAUCAUGUGUUAUCCUAAGAGUUGGGGUUUUUUAAAAUCUGUUUCACCAGGGGAAAAUAAAAGCAUCCCUAAUGUUCUUCCUCUAGUCAGUUUGCUUUGCUGAAAGCUCCCUGGAAAUUAGUACAGUUCUACAGGAAGCCAGAAGACUGUACUGUCUGUCCACACCAUGGUCUCCUCAGUCCCCUCCACGCCAGCCCCUCUUCCCCACACCUAGUAGGUGUGCUACACCUCCCUUUGCCAGUCAUCCCGCCAUGGAUGGGGAGCCUACUUGGUGCCCUGGCAAACCUGUUUACACUAAGGAGAUGCCCACAGGGAGCGGGAAGCUCCCAAACCCUCAGUCAUUCUCCAGCAGAGACCUUUGCUCUUGGCCAGGUUUGAAACGAUGUUCAACCUCGCCACGUCAAUGUCUCAGUAAAAGACACUAUAGAUAGUUAUGGACAAUACACUCCAAGAAUACUGGGCUUAUGGGUGGGUUGGUUUUUUGUUUUGUUUUGUUUUGUUUUCAAGUCAUGUCUUUAUCCCCAUAUAAUGGAGAAUGUGCCACUUGGCUAAUAAUGUGUUUUCAAAACUACAAGUUCAGUGAUGACAGGAAAGAGGGCUAAAGUAGUCCCACAGAGGCUGGUAGAAAAGGCGAAUCACACUUAAGCACCAGCAGGUUAAAAACCUGAAAGGGUGGCCCUGACAAUUCAGACUAUAGGUUUUACAGCAUGCCACUUGUGCAAUAGGAGGUCUAGGGUUGAAACUUUCAAGAACGAGAGGAGGUGAAGGAAGGAGACGUUUACUGCUCAAAUGCCAUGCAUUUCACUGCUUGCCACUGAACUUGUAUUUGAAUGACUUAGUAAUGCUUAAUAUAAUUGGGCAACUUUUUUAGCACUUUGGAAAGAGUCAUCAAUCUUUCUGGUAAAUUAUAAAAGUUUUCUGAGUGAGAAAAGGUGUGUUUGGAGUUUGUUUGACUUUUUAUAUUAUUAUUGUUAUUAAUAAAGAAAAAAAUCUACAGCAUUUUUCAGACUCCACCCUAGAAAAUAUGUACCCCUGAAUUUGGUUUGCAGUUUGAUACUCAGGGAAGGAUGUAUUCCAUAGAUAUCCUUUCCGUAUAAAACACUAACAUCUUUGAGAAAUUCACCUACCAACUAACUUCAAUUGUUGUCACUAUGCAUUCUUCAAUGAAAACUAGCUUAUUUUUCCAUAUAGUAAUGCAGUUAGGGUUCUCAGCACUUUCUUUCUUCUAUCCUUUUUUUAACUCUUCAUAUUAUGUUCAGAUGAUCAUACUGUCAAGGUUUGUGUACAUUACUGAAAAUUUGUAUUGUAUAAAGCUUUUUGCAUUACGAGGCUGUACAGGGUCAUUUUGACAGUAACUGGUAUAUUCCUUUGCAUCUUAUGUUGCAUUGCCAAUUUCUAGUGUAUCCAGUUUGAAAGUAUAAUAUACUCUAAUUAAAAAAAAAAAAAGGUUGGCUAUA